CUAAUCUUCCAGUUGCCCCCUAUUGACUUUAAACCAAAGCUUUGAUUCAUGACCACUGGGAUCCAGCCAGCGGGGGAUUUCUUUUCCUGAUGGACUGUACCCAGGAUCUCACAUUUGCUUAAGCAGCUCCCACAAUUGGGUUCUUAUAAAAGGACACGGAAGAGACAAGCUCAGUUUUCUCUGAAGGAGAAGGACUGCACUUAGAACUGCAUUUUGGCGACCUCUGAAAUUCAGUACUGCAGUGAAUGAGCUUCUGAUCUUGAGGUGAACUUAACAAAAUUAUUUUUGGAAAAAUCGUUGUGGGAACCAUUAAAAGAACUCCAGGAAACAUGAAUUCUGGAAUCUUACAGGUCUUUCAGGGGGAACUCAUCUGCCCCCUGUGCAUGAACUACUUCAUAGACCCGGUCACCAUAGACUGUGGGCACAGCUUUUGCAGGCCUUGUUUCUACCUCAACUGGCAAGACAUCCCAUUUCUUGUCCAGUGCUCUGAAUGCACAAAGUCAACCGAGCAGAUAAACCUCAAAACCAACAUUCAUUUGAAGAAGAUGGCUUCUCUUGCCAGAAAAGUCAGUCUCUGGCUAUUCCUGAGCUCUGAGGAGCAAAUGUGUGGCACUCACAGGGAGACAAAGAAGAUAUUCUGUGAAGUGGACAGGAGCCUGCUCUGUUUGCUGUGCUCCAGCUCUCAGGAGCACCGGUAUCACAGACACCGUCCCAUUGAGUGGGCUGCUGAGGAACACCGGGAGAAGCUUUUACAGAAAAUGCAGUCUUUGUGGGAAAAAGCUUGUGAAAAUCACAGAAACCUGAAUGUGGAAACCACCAGAACCAGAUGCUGGAAGGAUUAUGUGAAUUUAAGGCUAGAAGCAAUUAGAGCUGAGUAUCAGAAGAUGCCUGCAUUUCAUCAUGAAGAAGAAAAACAUAAUUUGGAGAUGCUGAAAAAGAAGGGGAAAGAAAUUUUUCAUCGACUUCAUUUAAGUAAAGCCAAAAUGGCUCAUAGGAUGGAGAUUUUAAGAGGAAUGUAUGAGGAGCUGAACGAAAUGUGCCAUAAACCAGAUGUGGAGCUACUUCAGGCUUUUGGAGACAUAUUACACAGGAGUGAGUCCGUGCUGCUGCACAUGCCCCAGCCUCUGAAUCCAGAGCUCAGUGCAGGGCCCAUCACUGGACUGAGGGACAGGCUCAACCAAUUCCGAGUGCAUAUUACUCUGCAUCAUGAAGAAGCCAACAAUGAUAUCUUUCUGUAUGAAAUUUUGAGAAGCAUGUGUAUUGGAUGUGACCAUCAAGAUGUACCCUAUUUCACUGCAACACCUAGAAGUUUUCUUGCAUGGGGUGUUCAGACUUUCACCUCGGGCAAAUAUUACUGGGAGGUCCAUGUAGGGGACUCCUGGAAUUGGGCUUUUGGUGUCUGUAAUAUGUAUCGGAAAGAGAAGAAUCAGAAUGAGAAGAUAGAUGGAAAGGCGGGACUCUUUCUUCUUGGGUGUGUUAAGAAUGACAUUCAAUGCAGUCUCUUUACCACCUCCCCACUUAUGCUGCAAUAUAUCCCAAAACCUACCAGCCGAGUAGGAUUAUUCCUGGAUUGUGAGGCUAAGACUGUGAGCUUUGUUGAUGUUAAUCAAAGCUCCCUAAUAUACACCAUCCCUAAUUGCUCUUUCUCACCUCCUCUCAGGCCUAUCUUUUGCUGUAUUCACUUCUGACCAGAGACAAAUCAGAAAUGUGUUCACAUGCUGUGGGAACCCCUUUAUCCCAGGAAGUCCUCUUCCUUGUGCCUUAACAUACAGGACAAAUAGGCUCUAUUUUAUGUCUUGAAUUGCCUUCUAAUGUUAUCAAAACUCAUUUAUUGUGUUACUAUUAAAUAUGCUGAAAACGCUAAAAGUAUACGUAUUGGUUCUUUAUUAAAUAAUUUUUGAAAAAUCAUUAUUCAUGAUCAUGGCAUACAGUAUAUUCUCUUUUUUUUCUUUAUUUAUGACUGUCACUGAGUGAAAUAAUAGAUGACAGACAUGUCUGAAUGAAGUAAAAAUCAAUGGAAGACAGUCGGGAUCUUUUGCUUCAUGCAAAAAACUUGGAGUGAAGUCUCAAUGAUAACUGGGAAAUGUUUUUCUUCCUCUUUAUCUAACUAUAUUACACUUAUCCAUCAGGUUUCAUUGUAUUAAUCUAUCCUUUGAGGUAAUA